GCCCAGCCGGUCACCGCCUGCCGGCUGCAGACGCCUGCGAGCAGGUUGUUUUUAUAAGAGGCGUCAUUGGCGCCCGAGCUGUGACCGCCGCCACUGGGGCAGCCAGCACAAUCGGGCGGAGGUGGCGCUGCCCCUUCAGGUACUGUACUAGGCGGGCUUAGACCCCGGGAGGGGGUUUGUGCCGACUGUCUGAGUCCCUGGCCGACACGCUCGGCUCAGUAGAGGAGCAGUGGCGGGGUCCGCCUCCUAGGCUGGGGCUGCUCGGGCGGGGACUUGACGCCUGGUGUCAGCGGCCGCACGGGCGACCUCCUCGGGCCGUGCGCGAGUGCACAGCUCCGGAGGCCCGAGCCGACCCUGGGGCGUCCGGUCCGGUGGUCUUGCAGCCUCCAAACCCCGAGUGCUAUACCGAACUGCGCGCCAAGGGUGGGAGAGCUGACGGCCUGGGCCACCCUUCUUCCUUCACUGGGCAGGCUUUGAGGUGCUUGUCGGUCUGGACUGAUGAAAAUCCAUAUGACCUGAAAGAUGUCUGAAAAUUCCAGUGACAGUGAUUCAUCUUGUGGUUGGACUGUCAUCAGUCAUGAGGGGUCAGAUAUAGAAAUGUUGAAUUCUGUGACCCCCACUGACAGCUGUGAGCCCGCCCCAGAAUGUUCAUCUUUAGAGCAAGAGGAGCUUCAAGCAUUGCAGAUAGAGCAAGGAGAAAGCAGCCAAAAUGGCACAGUGCUUAUGGAAGAAACUGCUUAUCCAGCUUUGGAGGAAACCAGCUCAACAAUUGAGGCAGAGGAACAAAAGAUACCCGAAGACAGUAUCUAUAUUGGAACUGCCAGUGAUGAUUCUGAUAUUGUUACCCUUGAGCCACCUAAGUUAGAAGAAAUUGGAAAUCAAGAAGUUGUCAUUGUUGAAGAAGCACAGAGUUCAGAAGACUUUAACAUGGGCUCUUCCUCUAGCAGCCAGUAUACUUUCUGUCAGCCAGAAACUGUAUUUUCAUCUCAGCCUAGUGACGAUGAAUCAAGUAGUGAUGAAACCAGUAAUCAGCCCAGUCCUGCCUUUAGACGACGCCGUGCUAGGAAGAAGACCGUUUCUGCUUCAGAAUCUGAAGACCGGCUAGUUGCUGAACAAGAAACUGAACCUUCUAAGGAGUUGAGUAAACGUCAGUUCAGUAGUGGUCUCAAUAAGUGUGUUAUACUUGCUUUGGUGAUUGCAAUCAGCAUGGGAUUUGGCCAUUUCUAUGGCACAAUUCAGAUUCAGAAGCGUCAACAGUUAGUCAGAAAGAUACAUGAAGAUGAAUUGAAUGAUAUGAAGGAUUAUCUUUCCCAGUGUCAACAGGAACAAGAAUCUUUUAUAGAUUAUAAGUCAUUGAAAGAAAAUCUUGCAAGGUGUUGGACACUUACUGAAGCAGAGAAGAUGUCCUUUGAAACUCAGAAAACGAACCUUGCUACAGAAAAUCAGUAUUUAAGAGUAUCCUUGGAGAAGGAAGAAAAAGCCUUAUCCUCAUUACAGGAAGAGUUAAACAAACUAAGAGAACAGAUUAGAAUAUUGGAAGAUAAAGGGACAAGUACUGAAUUAGUUAAAGAAAAUCAGAAACUUAAGCAGCAUUUGGAAGAGGAAAAGCAGAAAAAACACAGCUUUCUUAGUCAAAGGGAGACUCUGUUGACAGAAGCAAAGAUGCUAAAGAGAGAACUGGAGAGAGAACGACUAGUAACUACGGCUUUAAGGGGGGAACUCCAGCAGUUAAGUGGUAGUCAGUUACAUGGCAAGUCAGAUUCUCCCAAUGUAUAUACUGAAAAAAAGGAAAUAGCAAUCUUACGGGAAAGACUCACUGAGCUGGAACGGAAGCUAACCUUCGAACAGCAGCGUUCUGAUUUGUGGGAAAGAUUGUAUGUUGAGGCAAAAGAUCAAAAUGGAAAACAAGGAACAGAUGGAAAAAAGAAAGGGGGCAGAGGAAGCCACAGGGCUAAAAAUAAGUCAAAGGAAACAUUUUUGGGUUCAGUUAAGGAAACAUUUGAUGCCAUGAAGAAUUCUACCAAGGAGUUUGUAAGGCAUCAUAAAGAGAAAAUUAAGCAGGCUAAAGAAGCUGUGAAGGAAAAUCUGAAAAAAUUCUCAGAUUCAGUUAAAUCCACUUUCAGACACUUUAAAGAUACCACCAAGAAUAUCUUUGAUGAAAAGGGUAAUAAAAGAUUUGGUGCUACAAAAGAAGCAGCUGAAAAACCAAGAACAGUUUUUAGUGACUAUUUACAUCCACAGUAUAAGGCACCUACAGAAAACCAUCAUAAUAGAGGCCCUACUAUGCAAAAUGAUGGAAGGAAAGAAAAGCCAGUUCACUUUAAAGAAUUCAGAAAAAAUACAAAUUCAAAGAAAUGCAGUCCUGGGCAUGAUUGUAGAGAAAAUUCUCAUUCUUUCAGAAAGGCUUGUUCUGGUGUAUUUGAUUGUGCUCAACAAGAGUCCAUGAGCCUUUUUAACACAGUGGUGAAUCCUAUAAGGAUGGAUGAAUUUAGACAGAUAAUUCAAAGGUACAUGUUAAAAGAACUGGAUACUUUUUGUCACUGGAACGAACUUGAUCAGUUCAUCAAUAAGUUUUUCCUAAACGGUGUCUUUAUACAUGAUCAGAAGCUCUUCACUGACUUUGUUAAUGAUGUUAAAGAUUAUCUUAGAAACAUGAAGGAAUAUGAAGUAGAUAAUGAUGGAGUAUUUGAGAAGUUGGAUGAAUAUAUAUAUAGACACUUCUUUGGUCACACUUUUUCCCCUCCAUAUGGACCCAGGUCGGUUUACAUAAAACCGUGUCAUUACAGUAGUUUGUAACAUUUGUAGAUUGGAUAGCAUUUUUAUGAUUUGAUGAGUUUCUUGUAAGGUUACCGUUUCUAAGAGUUGUGCUUUAUGGCCACUGAGAGAAUUCAGAAUAAAUUGAAAGAUGGAGUCUAAAAAUUAUUAGCUGUUACAAAUGGAACAUUUCAUUAUAACGUGAUCACUUUGACUUGAGCAAAUGGUUUAAUUUUUAUCUUAAAAAUCAGUUAAGAAUAUAUAAAAUCCUACUUUGGCCAAGUUUGUUUCUUUUCAUUAUAGUUUAUAUGAAAAGAUCACCUUAAGUGAAAUUAUUUUCCUUUAAUCUUUUAUGUAUUUAUUCACUUUUGGAAGCUAGGAAUGAGCAACACAAAUUUUACUCUGAAGUCAGAAGAGCUCAUAUAUAAUAAUUCUAAUGUCCCACCUAUUUUCACUUGUCCAUUCCAUGUACCAGCUUAGUUAUGAUACUUAGUCACAUAAUUAUCUUUGAUAAAGGUAGAGGCACAAAGAGGCAAACUAAGCAAGUCAAAUUCUAAUGUGUGUACUUCAUAAUAAUUUUUUAUCCAUUUUCAUCUUUAUAUUCUGUAACAUGAAACUUACCUAAUCUUCAAAUGUUAGCUUCAUUUUUUACCUUUGAAAUACUUAAUCUUUCUGAAUAAAUAUAAUGUGUCUAUAAAAUAAUGAGACUGAUUCUGGUGUCUUUAGUCAUUAAGCUGGUAUCUAGUCCUAUAAUGAACAAAGGUGAAGCUGCCUUGAGGAGACAAGUGAAAAAUUUUUGCUUCAAAGGAGCUCACAAGCUAAGUAAAUAAAUGAAAUUAAGGUAUGGGGCAUGGUGGCCUCAGGCUGUCUGGAGGUGUUUGGAAAGGCUUCUUGAGUGAGGUGGCCUUUGAACUGAACUUAGUUUUUAAAGUAGCUUUUGGAAGAGAAAUGAGGAUUUGCUAUGCAGACAGGGAAGGGAAUUUCACUUAAAAGGAAGGUCAUUUGGAGAUGUGAAGAUACACUGCUUUAAGGAAGCAGGGUAGAGCUGGAGGAUAAGAGAUGCAGACCAUGAAGGGCCCCAUUUUAUGCUAAAGGUUUUGUCCUGUAGGACAUGGAGAACUUCUGAAGAAUUUUCAAGGCGGGUGGGAUAAGAUUAUAUUGUAUUUUAGAUUACAGUAGUCCCCCCUUAUCUUCAGGAUAUAUGUUCCAAGACCCCCAGUGGAUGCUGGAAACCAGGGAUAGAACAUAAUUCUAUAUAUACUAUGCAUGAAUUUCUUUUUCCUUCUUUACAAUCUCACACAUAGGUUUGUUCUUACUAUAGAUCUUACCAAUCUCAGCAUACUUUUAUUUCUCUUGAGAACCUUCACCCUUUCACUUAAAGGAGGCGCUUUAUAGCUUCUCUUUGGCAUAUCCAAAUGCCAGCAUCACUGUUGUAUUUUGGGGUCAUUAUUAAGUUACUUAAUCAUCCUUAAUCCUUAUCUUAGGGAUACUUGAACACAAACACUGUGGUAGGAUAACAGUAUAUCUGAUUAACAGACUGCUACUAGGUGAUUAAUGGGUGGGUAGUGUAAAUACACAAGAAAAGGAUGAUUCACAUCCCAUGUGGGAUGGAGCAGAACUGCAUUAUUUCAUUACAUUACUCAGAACAGGCAUAUAAUUGAAAACUUAUGAAUUAUUUUUUUUUAAUUAUUUGAGAUGGAAUCUUGCUUUGUCAGCCAGGCUGGAGUGCAGUGACACGAUCUCAGCUCACUGCAACCUCUGUCUCCUGGGUUCAGGUGAUUCUCCUCCCUAGUCUCCCAAGUAGCUGGGACUAUAGGCACGUGCCACCACACCCGGCUAAUUUUCAUAUUUUUAGUAGAGAUGGGGUUUCACCAUGUUGGCCAGGCUGUUCUUGAAAUCCUGACCUCAAGUGAUCCACACAUGUCUACCUCCCAAAGUGCUGGGAUUACAGUCGUGAGCCACUGUACCCCGCCUAAAACUGAUGAAUUAUUUCUGAAAUUUUCUAUUUAACAUUUUCAGACCACAGUUGACCACAGGUAACGGAAACCUCAAUCACAGAAAGUAAAGCCGUGGAUACGGUGGGACUAAUGUAUUGGUAGCAGCCUAGAGGAUUGAUGGGAAAGGUAUGAAGCUAGAAGGUGGUCAAUAUAAUACAGACAUGAGCUGAUGAACAUCUAAACUGGGACUAUACUAGUAGGAGAGGAAAGGAAAAAACAUUUGGAAAAUAGUAACAUUGAUAUUUCUUGUGAAGGAGAAGUAGAAAGUAACAGUGACUUCUAGAUUUCUGGGUUGGGUCAUCUUGUUGGAUAGUAGUACCACUGAGAUAGGGAAUUCAAGGUUUGGGGCAAGGGUAAUUGGAGAUGAGAAUUGUGUUUGGAGGUAACUACUGACAUUCAAGUGGAGAGGGUUAGUUGGCAGUUAGUUCUAUGGUCAUCUCUUUUGCCGAGACUGUAUAUUUAUCAGACUCCUGGGAGAACACCAACAUCCAUGGGGUUGUAGGGAAGGCUAAGGACAGGAGUGGGGAGUGGUACCUUGAAAAUCCAAAAGCCAUCUCAAGUAAAAGGAAUAAAUGUGUCAUGCUUUUUAAAAAGUUGAUGUGCGGAAAAUGUUUUCUUGGCUUGGAAACUGGGCGGCCAGGGGAUGACAGUAUGGACUUCCAGUGAAGUAGUGACGGAAGCCUGAUCAUAGACAUUAAGGAAAGCGGUGUAGGUGUUGUGAGCUUUUGCUGUAAGAAAAAGUUGAGACUUUUGUUUUGCUUUGUUUGUGAGAGAUGUGUAUGUAUUUCUGCUGAGUGAUAAAGCCAGCGGGGAGGGACUGAUUUUUAUAGGAAAGGAGGAAAAAUAAUGGAAACACAUCUCAUUAUUUUAUUGUCACAUUUCUUUUCUUUGUUAUCUUUUGAGUGUUUCCCUUUUUUGCCAGUAGAGUUAUUGUCUAUUUUUUCUUUCUAUAGGACAAAAAAACUAAUACAGACUCCUUUAUUUUUAUAUGGAUAUACUAGGAUUGUAAUUCAGAUAUUUAAUAUCUUUUAUCAGUGUUCAGAUCAUAGAUUAAUGGAGAAAACAUUUAAAAUUGUUUUAAAUUUAAAUACAUUGAACUCUAACAUAGAUGAAAAAUGUGUUUACUGCUUUCAGUCGACCUGAUAAAAAGCAACGUAUGGUAAAUAUUGAAAACUCCAGGCAUCGAAAACAAGAGCAGAAGCACCUUCAGCCACAGCCUUAUAAAAGGGAAGGUAAAUGGCAUAAAUAUGGUCGCACUAAUGGAAGACAAAUGGCAAAUCUUGAAAUAGAAUUGGGGCAAUUACCUUUUGAUCCUCAAUACUGAUUCACAAUUGAGUUAAAUUAGACAACUGUAAGAGAAAAAUUUAUGCUUUGUAUAAUGUUUGGUAUUGAAACUAAUGAAAUUACCAAGAUGACAAUGUCUUUUCUUUUGUUUCUAAGUAUCAGUUUGAUAACUUUAUAUUAUUCCUCAGAAGCAUUAGUUAAAAGUCUACUAACCUGCAUUUUCCUGUAGUUUAGCUUCGUUGAAUUUUUUUUGACACUGGAAAUGUUCAACUGUAGUUUUAUUAAGGAAGCCAGGCAUGCAACAGAUUUUGUGCAUGAAAUGAGACUUCCUUUCAGUGUAAGAGCUUAAAGCAAGCUCAGUCAUACAUGACAAAGUGUAAUUAACACUGAUGUUUGUGUUAAAUUUGCAGCAGAGCUUGAGAAAAGUACAUUGUUCUGGAAUUUCAUCAUUAACAUUUUAUAAUCUUACACUCACUUCUUGUCUUUUUGUGGGUUCAAGAGCCCUCUGACUUGUGAAGAAUUUGCUGCCCUCUUAAGAGCUUGCUGACUUGUUUUCUUGUGAAAUUUUUUGCACAUCUGAAUAUCGUGGAAGAAACAAUAAAACUACACCAUGAGGAAAACUAAAGGUCUUUAUUUAAAAUCUGGCAUUGUAUUAACAUGUAAUUUUAUACUAUGUGGUAUUUUAUACAUUUCCUCAGUAGUGAUAUUUGGUAAAGCAGUUCAUACAGCUUUUUUCUAAGUUCCAUGAAUCUUACCCAGUGUUUACCGAAGUAUUUAAGCAGCAUCUGAAUAUUUCCACCCAGCAAUGUUAAUUUAUCUAGGAAAGUUCAGAAUUUCAUCUUCAUGUUGAAUUUCCCUUUUAACUUCCGUUCAUAGACAUAUAUGUGACUUCCAAUUCGACCCUCUGGCAAGUGAGUGUGGAAGAAAACAGCAGUUCUUUUAUAAUUGCUUGAAAUUAGGAAAGCGCUUAUUUCCUAGAAGCAAAUAAAUGUUUAAGUAAAUAAAGGCUACAUUUUGCUGA